AUCCCAGAAGCUGCUGUUAGCUCGCCGGUCCUCGGCACGCCGCCCGUUCGCCCCUGCGCUGUCCGCCCUUCCCCUAGCGUUACUUCCGGUCCCUCGCUGAGGGGGUUCGUGCGGCUCCCAGGAGGCGUGAACCGCGGACCAUGAGCGUGGGCUUCAUCGGGGCCGGCCAGCUGGCCUAUGCUCUGGCGCGGGGCUUCACGGCCGCAGGCAUCCUGUCGGCUCACAAGAUAAUAGCCAGCUCCCCAGAAAUGAACCUGCCCACGGUGUCCGCGCUCAGGAAGAUGGGUGUGAACCUGACACGCAGCAACAAGGAGACGGUGAAGCACAGCGACGUCCUGUUUCUGGCUGUGAAGCCACAUAUCAUCCCCUUCAUCCUGGAUGAGAUUGGGGCCGACGUGCAAGCCAGACACAUCGUGGUCUCCUGUGCGGCUGGUGUCACCAUCAGCUCUGUGGAGAAGAAGCUGAUGGCAUUCCAGCCAGCCCCCAAAGUGAUUCGCUGCAUGACCAACACACCUGUGGUAGUGCAGGAAGGCGCUACAGUGUACGCCACGGGCACCCAUGCCCUGGUGGAGGAUGGGCAGCUCCUGGAGCAGCUCAUGAGCAGCGUGGGCUUCUGCACUGAGGUGGAAGAGGACCUCAUCGAUGCCGUCACGGGGCUCAGUGGCAGCGGGCCUGCCUAUGCAUUCAUGGCUCUGGACGCAUUGGCUGAUGGUGGGGUGAAGAUGGGUUUGCCACGGCGCCUGGCAAUCCAACUCGGGGCCCAGGCUUUGCUGGGAGCUGCCAAGAUGCUGCUGGACUCGGAGCAGCAUCCAUGCCAGCUUAAGGACAAUGUCUGCUCCCCUGGGGGAGCCACCAUCCACGCCCUGCACUUUCUAGAGAGUGGGGGCUUCCGCUCUCUGCUCAUCAAUGCAGUUGAGGCCUCCUGUAUCCGAACACGAGAGCUACAGUCCAUGGCCGACCAAGAAAAGAUCUCCCCAGCUGCCCUUAAGAAGACCCUCUUAGACAGAGUGAAGCUGGAAUCCCCCACAGUCUCCACACUGACCCCCUCCAGCCCAGGGAAGCUCCUCACAAGAAGCCUGGCCCUGGGAGGCAAGAAGGACUAAGGCAGCAUCUGUCCCCUCUGUGAUUCAGAGCCCUUAGUUGAGAGCCCCUGCCGCCCCUGCCACCCCCCUGCCCCGCUCCCACCAUUGCCCCUCCUCAGCUGUGCAAGGAGAAAGCAUGCUUAGGAAGUUUUCAGGUCCUUGUGAUAAAACCUCCUUAAAUCUGUUCAGACCAAGCAAUGCGAGCUUCCUCUCCUGUCCCAUGUUGGAAGUUGCUCUGAAGGGGUGGUAGAUGCUGGAAGCCAGACACAACCCUGCGUACGCUGCUCAGUUGGUGGAGACUGGGGCUGGGACUGGAGUCAGCCCAGCUGGGAGGAGGGGCUGGGGAGGAUCUGCAGCUGAAGCCCGAGGCAGGGUUGGUGUGAUGCCAAGGCAAAGUGGUGAGGAGAAAACAGGAAACGGGCUUUCUCUGAAUUGGUAAAUGGGAAAGAAGUGAGCAACUUAAGAUUGUCACAAUUAAUCACAAGUGUACAGGAUUAGACUGGGUUUAUAUUUAACUCUUGCUUCAUAGGUGUACCAUUUAAAGAGUGUUAUUUAAUGCUAAGUUUAACUGCUUUAAUAAAGUUUAUUUUUAAAUAUC